AGUUUGAAGGCUAAUCUGAAAGAGGAAGAAGAAUCUGUAUAUCUGUAUAUAUUGGCUAGCAAAUGUGCCCUGCUCUCUCCCCUCUUAAAAAUAGCAGCAACCCAUCUUUGCAAAGAAGCUUGCCUAUAGAGCAGGCACUCUGUGAAUGGACUGUGCUUUUACGACCCUACAGGGUAUCAAGAUACUGUGCAGCUCGCCAACAAGGAUUAAUUGCAAGGACUGGUAGAUCGAAUUUACUGAAGACUUGGAGCUUGCUUCUGAGAACAAACGCAAAAGGACAGUAAACUGUGGACCUUGAAGUUAGCAGCAGAAGGAAGGCAUCUAUUUUGGACUUGCAAGCUGUGCAGCCUGGGAUAAGAAGAAGGAUGAUAUAAGCGCUCUCUUGGCCUGCGUGGGCUUCCUCUAAUAUUACACCGUAAAAGGCAUUGAUCACCAUAAGAAGGAACAUUUGUGAAGGUACUCCAGUGCCAGAAAGAGGCACAAAGCAGACAUUCGUAGAGAAACAUGGAUGAAACAGGAAAUCUGACAGUAUCUUCUGCCACAUGCCAUGACACUAUUGAUGACUUCCGCAAUCAAGUGUAUUCCACCUUGUACUCUAUGAUCUCUGUUGUAGGCUUCUUUGGCAAUGGCUUUGUGCUCUAUGUCCUCAUAAAAACCUAUCACAAGAAGUCAGCCUUCCAAGUAUACAUGAUUAAUUUAGCAGUAGCAGAUCUACUUUGUGUGUGCACACUGCCUCUCCGUGUGGUCUAUUAUGUUCACAAAGGCAUUUGGCUCUUUGGUGACUUCUUGUGCCGCCUCAGCACCUAUGCUUUGUAUGUCAACCUCUAUUGUAGCAUCUUCUUUAUGACAGCCAUGAGCUUUUUCCGGUGCAUUGCAAUUGUUUUUCCAGUCCAGAACAUUAAUUUGGUUACACAGAAAAAAGCCAGGUUUGUGUGUGUAGGUAUUUGGAUUUUUGUGAUUUUGACCAGUUCUCCAUUUCUAAUGGCCAAACCACAAAAAGAUGAGAAAAAUAAUACCAAGUGCUUUGAGCCCCCACAAGACAAUCAAACUAAAAAUCAUGUUUUGGUCUUGCAUUAUGUGUCAUUGUUUGUUGGCUUUAUCAUCCCUUUUGUUAUUAUAAUUGUCUGUUACACAAUGAUCAUUUUGACCUUACUAAAAAAAUCAAUGAAAAAAAAUCUGUCAAGUCAUAAAAAGGCUAUAGGAAUGAUCAUGGUCGUGACCGCUGCCUUUUUAGUCAGUUUCAUGCCAUAUCAUAUUCAACGUACCAUUCACCUUCAUUUUUUACACAAUGAAACUAAACCCUGUGAUUCUGUCCUUAGAAUGCAGAAGUCCGUGGUCAUAACCUUGUCUCUGGCUGCAUCCAAUUGUUGCUUUGACCCUCUCCUAUAUUUCUUUUCUGGGGGUAACUUUAGGAAAAGGCUGUCUACAUUCAGAAAGCAUUCUUUGUCCAGCGUGACUUAUGUACCCAGAAAGAAGGCCUCUUUGCCAGAAAAAGGAGAAGAAAUAUGUAAAGUAUAGUUUAAACCCAUUUCCAGUCCAAACCAAUGAAAAUAGUUUCCCAAAUAAGUAUUUUGUCAAAUCAUUUACAAAAAAAAUAAAAAUUUUACUUAAUAUUUUACAAAUACUUAACUAUUUGGGCCUACAACUCUAUCUCAUUUAUGCAUCCACAUGAUUAGAUAUUUAUAGAUAUUUUAAGUGCUAAAAAUUCGGUCCACAACUAUGAACUGAAUUAUAAAUAAUUUUGACCACUCACCAGAAUUUGGAGAAUAUUUUUAUCUUUGCACUAUAAAAUAUGUCUUAUAUUAAAGUUUUCCUCUUCAAAUAAAAGCUUUACAAACGAUAAAAUAUAUAAAAUUAGUCAAUAAAAAUACAUGCAAGCUAAAAGUUAUAAAAUAUAAAACUAGAUAUAAAAUUGGCAAAUAGUUCUGAAUCAUUCUAACAUAUUCCUUUGCAUGCAUGCCAUCAGAUGAGAACUGGAGAUGACUCAGGAGCUACAUAAAACGUACUGUCACCCUUCUUUGUAGUACUGAUUCGCUAGGCAAAUUAGGGCCAUUUCUUCCAAAAGAGAAUGUAAAAGUGCUAGAACAGACUAGUAUUCAGCUAAAGGGUCCUAAAAGCACCAUACAAUGUUCAAUAUGGCAACAGGAGAAAUCUGGUCAAAAGCCAGUUUGUCUCCAGUUUUCUUCUGCCUUUGCCUCAGGCUCCCAAAAUUGAAUAGUGGAGUUUUAGCUGCUCAGUGAGGUUCCUGUAGAGAUUUCUCUCCAUCCAUGACAUAUAAUUCUUCCUUAAGAAGCCAGACAACUGGCACUCCUAUAUAUAAAUAGAAGUAAUUAAAAACUUAUCUGAAGAAGAGAAAAGGAAAAGGAAUCUACUUUUCUAUAUGCCAAUUGCUGGGAUCAAAAUAAACUACAAAGGAUUUAUGAAGAAAAUUGUGAAUGUUCACAUUACAAAUUCUUUUAAGAAGUGCAUACAUUUAUGUAUAUGUAUACAACUAUAUGUAAGAGAUUUUGCUGUAUGAUAUGCAUUAUGGGUGAAAGUUCACGAUAAGUUUUAUUAUUGCUUUAUUACUUUUUAUUGGUAUGUUGACAGGAAUAUCAUGGAUAUGUUUACAGUGACUUUUAUAUUACAGUGGACGCUUUGAUCUUAAAACAGCCACAACAACUCAUCUACGGCUGAAAUAUAAUAUGCGUGGACAAGCUUUUGCUGAAGUGUAGUGUGUCCUUUAAGUUUGUUUUUUAAAAAGUAACUUACCUCAGAAGAAAUAAAUAACUAUAAAGAAAAAA